GCAGAGCAGCGUCAGAGCCGCGCAGGGGACGGGAGUGAGAGCAGGAGCGACGCAGAGCGGCCGUCGCCGUGCCCGGGUCUCAGGGCGCCUGGCUGAAGUGAGCAUGGCUUCAGUGGCCUGGGCCGUCCUCAAGGUGCUGCUGCUUCUCCCCACUCAGACUUGGAGCCCCGUGGGAGCAGGAAAUCCACCUGACUGUGAUGCCCCACUGGCCUCUGCCUUGCCUAGGUCAUCCUUCAGCAGCUCCUCAGAGCUGUCCAGCAGCCACGGCCCGGGGUUUUCAAGGCUUAAUCGAAGAGAUGGAGCUGGUGGCUGGACUCCACUUGUGUCAAAUAAAUACCAAUGGCUGCAAAUUGACCUUGGAGAGAGAAUGGAGGUCACUGCUGUCGCCACCCAAGGAGGAUAUGGGAGCUCUGACUGGGUGACCAGCUACCUCCUGAUGUUCAGUGAUGGUGGGAGAAACUGGAAGCAGUAUCGCCGAGAAGAAAGCAUCUGGGGUUUUCCAGGAAACACAAACGCAGACAGUGUGGUGCACUACAGACUCCAGCCUCCCUUUGAAGCCAGGUUCCUGCGCUUUCUCCCUUUAGCCUGGAACCCUAGGGGCAGGAUUGGGAUGCGGAUCGAAGUGUACGGAUGUGCAUAUAAAUCUGAGGUGGUUUAUUUUGAUGGACAAAGUGCUCUGCUGUAUAGACUUGAUAAAAAACCUUUAAAACCAAUAAGAGACGUUAUUUCUUUGAAAUUUAAAGCCAUGCAGAGCAAUGGAAUUCUACUUCACAGAGAAGGACAACAUGGAAAUCACAUUACUCUGGAAUUAAUUAAAGGAAAGCUUGUCUUUUUUCUUAAUUCAGGCAAUGCUAAGCUGCCUUCCACUAUUGCUCCUGUGACCCUCACCCUGGGCAGCCUGCUGGACGACCAGCACUGGCAUUCCGUCCUCAUCGAGCUCCUCGACACGCAGGUCAACUUCACCGUGGACAAACACACUCAUCAUUUCCAAGCAAAGGGAGAUUCCAGUUACUUGGAUCUUAAUUUUGAGAUCAGCUUUGGGGGAAUUCCGACACCCGGAAGAUCGCGGGCAUUCAGACGUAAAAGCUUUCAUGGGUGUUUAGAAAAUCUUUAUUAUAAUGGAGUGGAUGUUACCGAAUUAGCCAAGAAACACAAACCACAGAUCCUCAUGAUGGGAAAUGUGUCCUUCUCAUGUCCACAGCCACAGACUGUCCCUGUGACUUUUCUGAGCUCCAGGAGUUAUCUGGCUCUGCCAGGCAACUCUGGGGAGGACAAAGUGUCUGUCACUUUUCAAUUUCGAACGUGGAACAGAGCAGGACAUUUGCUUUUCGGCGAACUUCGACGUGGUUCAGGGAGUUUCGUCCUCUUUCUUAAGGAUGGCAAGCUCAAACUGAGUCUCUUCCAGCCGGGACAGUCACCAAGGAAUGUCACAGCAGGUGCUGGAUUAAACGAUGGGCAGUGGCACUCUGUGUCCUUCUCUGCCAAGUGGAGCCAUAUGAAUGUGGUGGUGGACGAUGACACAGCUGUUCAGCCCCUGGUGGCUGUGCUCAUUGAUUCAGGUGACACCUAUUAUUUUGGAGGCUGCCUGGACAACAGCUCUGGCUCUGGAUGUAAAAGCCCCCUGGGAGGGUUUCAGGGCUGCCUAAGGCUCAUCACCAUUGGUGACAAAGCGGUGGAUCCCAUCUUAGUACAGCAGGGGGCGCUGGGGAGUUUCAGGGACCUCCAGAUAGACUCCUGCGGCAUCACAGACAGGUGCUUGCCCAGCUACUGUGAGCAUGGGGGCGAGUGUUCCCAGUCGUGGGACACCUUCUCCUGUGACUGUCUAGGCACAGGCUAUACGGGCGAGACCUGCCAUUCCUCUCUCUACGAGCAGUCUUGUGAAGCCCACAAGCACCGAGGGAACCCGUCUGGGCUUUACUAUAUUGAUGCAGAUGGAAGUGGCCCCCUGGGACCAUUUCUUGUGUACUGCAAUAUGACAGCAGACGCCGCGUGGACGGUGGUGCAGCACGGUGGCCCCGACGCGGUGACCCUCCGAGGUGCCCCCAGCGGGCACCCGCGCUCGGCUGUGUCCUUCGCGUACGCAGCGGGCGCGGGGCAGCUGCGGUCCGCGGUGAACCUGGCGGAGCGCUGCGAGCAGCGGCUGGCUCUGCGCUGCGGGACGGCGCGGCGCCCGGACUCACGAGAUGGAACCCCACUGAGCUGGUGGGUUGGAAGAACCAAUGAAACACACACUUCCUGGGGAGGUUCUCUGCCUGAUGCUCAAAAGUGUACUUGUGGAUUAGAGGGGAACUGCAUUGAUUCUCAGUAUUACUGCAACUGUGAUGCUGGCCGGAAUGAAUGGACUAGUGACACAAUAGUCCUUUCCCAAAAGGAGCACCUGCCAGUCACUCAGAUUGUGAUGACAGACGCAGGCCGACCACAUUCCGAAGCAGCUUAUACACUGGGGCCACUGCUCUGCCGCGGAGAUCAGUCAUUCUGGAAUUCAGCUUCCUUCAACACUGAGACUUCAUACCUUCAUUUCCCUGCUUUCCACGGAGAACUCACUGCUGACGUGUGCUUCUUUUUUAAGACCACAGUUUCCUCCGGGGUGUUUAUGGAGAACCUGGGGAUCACAGAUUUCAUCAGGAUUGAGCUGCGUGCUCCCACAGAAGUGACCUUUUCCUUCGAUGUGGGGAAUGGACCUUGUGAGGUCACGGUGCAGUCACCCACUCCCUUUAAUGACAAUCAGUGGCACCACGUGAGGGCAGAGAGAAAUGUUAAAGGAGCGUCUCUUCAAGUUGAUCAGCUUCCUCAGAAGAUGCAGCCUGCCCCUGCUGAUGGGCACGUUCGUUUACAGCUCAACAGCCAGCUCUUCAUUGGUGGAACGGCCACCAGACAGAGAGGCUUUCUAGGAUGCAUUCGGUCUCUGCAGUUGAACGGGGUGGCCCUGGAUCUGGAAGAAAGAGCCACAGUGACGCCAGGAGUGGAGCCAGGGUGUGCAGGACACUGCAGCACCUAUGGACACUUGUGUCGCAAUGGAGGGAGAUGCAGAGAGAAACGCAGGGGGGUCACCUGUGACUGUGCCUUCUCAGCCUAUGAUGGGCCGUUCUGCUCCAAUGAGAUUUCCGCAUAUUUUGCAACUGGCUCCUCAAUGACAUACCAUUUUCAAGAACAUUACACUUUAAGUGAAAACUCCAGCUCUCUCGUUUCUUCAUUACACAGAGAUGUAACAUUGACCAGAGAAAUGAUCACACUGAGCUUCCGAACCACACGAACUCCGAGCUUAUUGCUGUAUGUGAGCUCUUUCUAUGAGGAAUACCUUUCAGUUAUCCUCGCCAACAAUGGAAGUUUGCAGAUUAGGUACAAGCUAGAUAGACAUCAAAAUCCUGAUGCAUUUACCUUUGAUUUUAAAAACAUGGCUGAUGGGCAACUUCACCAAGUGAAGAUUAACAGAGAAGAAGCUGUGGUCAUGGUAGAGGUUAACCAGAGCACAAAGAAACAAGUCAUCUUGUCCUCAGGGACAGAAUUCAACGCCGUCAAAUCUCUCAUAUUGGGAAAGGUUUUAGAGGCUGCCGGCGCGGACCCGGACACAAGGCGGGCGGCGACUAGUGGCUUCACUGGCUGCCUCUCGGCGGUGCGCUUCGGCCGCGCUGCUCCCCUGAAGGCGGCGCUGCGCCCCAGCGGCCCCUCCCGGGUCACCGUCCGCGGCCACGUGGCCCCUAUGGCCCGCUGCGCAGCGGGGGCGGCGUCCGGCUCCCCGGCGCGGGAACUGGCUCCCCGACUCGCGGGGGGCGCAGGUCGUUCUGGACCAGCGGAUGAGGGAGAGCCCUUGGUUAAUGCAGACAGAAGAGACUCUGCUGUCAUCGGAGGUGUGAUAGCAGUGGUGAUAUUUAUUUUGCUUUGCAUCACUGCCAUAGCCAUACGCAUCUAUCAACAGAGAAAGUUACGCAAAGAAAAUGAGUCAAAAGUCUCAAAAAAAGAAGAGUGCUAGGACAGCUCUAAACAGUGAGCUCGAUGUGCAAAACGCAGUCCAUGAAAACCAGAAAGAGCGAGUCUUCUGAUUGGCAGCUGUGGCUGUCUCUAUCAUCGUGACUGUGGACUUCCCUGCUGUUGCCAUCAGGGUGCACACAAGCAGGUGCAGUGCUGUCACCUGGCUGAAGACCUGCAGCCUCGGAGCCUCUGGGAGGUCCCUUUCUCCCUCGGUGAAACACAGUCCUCCACAUCAAUUUCCAAACAAUGAAUUAGGUAUGGCCAUUCAUCACUGUUCAGUAGUUUCCCCGUCCAAAGGCUCUCUUCCAAAACUGCAGUUUGAUCUGUGUUAAUAAUUGUGGGGUUUUAGAUGAGAAAAUGGCUAUAAAGCUGUGGCCCUACUUUAUUUUUUAAAAAUGACAGAACUUUUGUUCAGAUGUAAAAGACAAAAUUGCACUUUAAUGUUUUUUGUUACUUGAAAACAUAUCUGGGAUCCCUUUUUUUGGUCCUCUGCUGAUAUUUAUAAAACAAGAAAUGCUUCUUGGACUACCUUCACUGGCAUUUCCAUAGUCCUGGAAUCCAGAGCCAAGUGGCCUAUCUAAAAUUCACAGCCCUUUUAUUCUCCUGUGUGAUGGUUAAUACAACACAGUUGAAGCCUGGAAACACUACCAUUAUUUUUGGUGUAUUGCUUUUUCUAAUUGACUGUUUUUAAUGAUUUUGAUACAUUUUAAUGUUGAAAUUAAUAUUGAAUGUUAGCUAUGAAAUUUUAGUAUUGAAUUUUAUAAUGGAACAGAACAUUGGUAGGUAACAAGAUGCAAGAGGAUGUCAAUACAAGAUUGUCUGCCUGUUUUUCUUUGUAAUUUGUAAUUACAGUUUUUGUAACUUGUGAUUAUGUUUUUAACUAAAUUUACCACCAGAUACAAACAAUACUUCUUACACAGAGUUAUCCUUUAUUUAUAUCAUUAAGACGUGAAUGAAACAUCAUCCUAACUUACUUCCCCAAGAUAUUGAGAGGUCAUAUCUGUUUUUCUUUAUCAUUCAUUUCUUUUUCUAAAAGUUGUUACUGAUAUGCUUUUGAUUUCCUAUGACUCUAUUAUGUUGUACAGAACAUCUUUUCAAUUUAUUAAAAAAAUAGCUUAACUGAAGAUCACUAAUUCCUUUUCUAAAUUUUGAACUGCUCUAGGCAUAAAUAUCAUUGUGUAUUAUCCUUUCAUCUAAUCACUUUUGGAAUGUAAACUGAAGACUGUUCACUCCAAGUUAAGUUAGCAUUUACAUGAUGUUUAUUAAAUCUGCCAGUCUGAUCACAGGUUUAUGACCAUGGGGCCAAAUUCCCAUAGAUUACCCAAAAUUGAAUAUGUGCAGUUAACUGGAACAUGUCUCAUUAAGGUUUACAUACACACUAAGACAGCAAAGGAUUGGAAUUAACUUUAUGGAGACAGUUCCAGGGACUAGUAUUGAAGCAGUGGUUAUUUGAUAAUGCAUGGAACCACCAUUUGGAUUCAAUAAACCAAUUACAUAAAAGCAAUGAUGCUACACUCUUCAUAUUCCAGAUACCAACUGCCUACCAAGGACUAAUGAGAUGGUAUAUUUCUUCCACAUCAGGGCAAGCUGAAAAUAUAUUGAUUCAGCGUUACUGUUACGUAAAUGAAUUUCCAUCUUGUUAUGGAAAUUCGUAUGUGUUAUUUUUGAAAGAAUGAAUACACUCUCUGUCUUAAAUCCGCUCUUAACAAAUGAUCUCUUCUCAGAAUACUACAUCUGUAUUGAGAGUACAGACAGCCCAUUGGUCACUGCACCUUUUGCAAGACAGCGAAACGGAUGCAUCAAAUUGCAUUGAUACAUCAUCACCAUCAAUCUUUUGCACUGAUUUUUAGACUUAAUCUUCUUAUUUGAAAAUAAACUCAUUUUUAAAUAAAAUAAAAAAUAUUUUAGGGAAAGCUCUAUAAAAUUAAAAUUACAGAAUUAUAUGCUUUUUAAAAUUUAUGCAAAAAUGUGCAGACAAAUGUAUUCUGUAUUGGUUUAUGUAUCACUUUGCCCUUGUAUAUUUUGAGAUUAUUAAGAUUUGUUGACUUUUUUGGUUUGAUAUUUAUCAUCUGUUAAAUUUUUCCUUUUAAAUUAUUAAAUGCAAAGUGCAAGAAAAAGAGAUAAAUAUUUACUGAUUGCUAGAUGUAAAAAUAUCUAUGAAUAUAUAUAUUUAAACUUCUGCCAAAGAGCAACCAUCUAACAGUCAACUUACUAAAAUCUAAAUUGAGUACUUUUUACUGUUGCAGAGAAUUAAGUCACUAAACGUUAUUUAGAUACAUAGAUGCUAGUUGCAAGUAACACCCUUUUGUAACAUAAAAGUAAAAGCAUAAUAAUUUCCCAACUUUUUUCUUCAAAUUAAAAAAGAAAAUAGCAUAUAAUUACCAUUCUUCAUUUGAGAAAGCUGAAGAUUCUGAUGCUUAAAAACUUCAGAAUUCUAAUAUUAAAAAUAGAGUGGUUCAUGUGACAUUGAAGGCUUAUCUCUGUAAAAUAGUGACACUGGUGAGUGGUAUUAUCUCAAUAUUUUUGUCCAAAUUCACCUUAGGAAAUCACUGUAAAUCUUCAUUGUUUACUAAAAGUCAUUAUUACGGCAUAAACUUAACAUACUUUGAUAGUAGUUACUACUGAUACGUGACAUAUUCUACCCCGUGUCUCUAUUACUCUGUCUCUAUUACUGUGAAAAGUCACAGUAAAUUUAACAUUUUCUUCCAGACUGUGUAUGAUCUUUCAUUGUAAUAGAGACAUGGAGUAGGAUAAGUCAUGUAUUAACAUGUAAGAUUUUUUUAACCUGCUCCCUCAGUUUUAUAGAUGAGACAAAGAUAAGGUUGUAAGAGCUAAUCUCUUCAAGUAGGCAGUACUAGUAAGUUGUCAUGCGUGGACUGAACUCCUGGCACUUCUCUCUCUUAACUUCAAUCCAUAGAGAAGCCCACCUUCCUGCCUUCCCAGUAUUAUUUAGCAGAGGAGAAAAUCAUAUUAGGCUGUUUGAUACUGUUUGCCUAGACUGACCAAUAAUUCUGGAUCUUUGUUCACAUCUUCUCUGAAAGAAUAUUUGAUGGGAAAUCUUUUUUAUUUUUUAAUUUUUGUGUACAUACUAGGUGUAUAUAUUUAUGGAGUACAUGAAAUGUUUUGAUACAGGCAUGCACUGUGAAAUAAGCACAUCAUGGAGAAUGGGGUAUCCAUCCCCUCAACAUUUAUCCUUUGUGUUACAAACAACCUGAUUACACUCUGUAUUUUAAAAUAUGCAGUUAAGUUUUUAUUGACUAUAGUCACCCUAUUGUGCUAUCAUAUAGUAAGUUUUACUCAUUCUUUCUACUUUUUUUGUACCCAUUAACCUAUCCCCACCUCUGCCCCACCAUUAUCUCAGCUGUCUACUACUUUUUUCAGCCUUUACUAACCAUCCUUCUACUCUAUAUCCAUGAAUUCCGUUGUUUUGAUUUUUAGAUCCCACAAAUAAAUGAGAACAUGGCAAUGUUUGUCUUUCUAUGCCUGGCCUAUUUCACUUAACAUAAUGACCUCCAGUUCCAUCCAUGCUGUCGCAAGUGACAGGAUCUCAUUCUCUUUUAUGGCUGAAGAGUACUCCAUUUUGUAUGUGAACCACAUUUUCUUCAUUCAUCUGUUGAUGAACACUUAGGGUGUUUCCAAAUCUUAGCUGUUAUAAACAGUAUUGCAACAAAUAAAAGAGUGCAGAUGGAAAAUUGAUUUUGAUGGCUUUUUUCUUUAAUAAAACAUUAAUUUCUUCAUGUAUAACUGGAAGGCAAACAAAUGAUCCAUUUGCUUAGUUUAUUCUUGAAUCCAUAAUAUAAGUAACAGAAAUGGAUUAUUAAAAUAUACUUGAAUUUGGGGAAGAAUGAUAUGGACACAUUUUAAAUCAAAACAUGAUGAAUUGGCUGUUUAACCUACUACCUCAUUGGCCAAUCUGGGGCAAGAUGAAAGUAUUUGUAAACACUGUUUUGGCAAUUAUGUGUAAAGAGAGAACCAAUUUUUUAAUUAAAAAAUUGAAUUCUAAGAAUUACAGAGCUUUUCUAUUGGUAAAGACAUUAAAUAUCAUAGAGUCCAACGCUUUUCUCUUCCUUCACAUCACUCCCAAUGGAUGUAGCUCAGGCUAAGUUCAUUGCUGAUGUGUUGUCAGAACAGCCACUCACGGUUUAAGUUGGUAUACUUAAGUGCAAAUGUAACCUUAAGAAGGUUACAUAAAGUUGCCAUUACUAGGAGUAGUAGCAGAAUUUAUUAUGGAUUAAUCAUAUCGUCGGGAAAAUGUACUGAAGCACUACUUCCUGUGGUAUUUUUUUUACAAAAUGAUAACAUAGUUUAUUGCCUAUAGGUUAUGACCUAAAAUUAUAUUUUUGCAUUUUAUUGUGCCAUUAUAUAUUUUAAAAUGUGAGGUUCACAUGGUUGCAUUUGCUCUGUGAAUAAAAAUGUUUAAAAUCAUAAGAUGAACUUUUAGAUUUUGCGAUAUGAAAAUUUCUAACUUAGCUAGCUUGUGAUGGUACCUAAAAAUUUAAGAAAGCCCUUAAAAUAGAACCUCUGUGACUGCAUGAGCACUUUGUAUGACUCAUAUCACAUUUUAACUCCUUAAGCAAGCCAAUGAGGUAAAACAUAUAAUUGUCCCCAUUUUUGCAAAAUUCACAAAGGCCUUCACUGCUUUGAGAAAACAUUACACAGAUAAUUACUGACAAAAAUGGGUUAGAAUGCAGGUCCUGAGAUGUCUAGUUCCUGACCAAUUCUACAGGUUGCCUUGCUCCCAUAAUAUGCUCCAAUCUACAAUGUUCAUCUUAAUCUGCAGUGAGUAAACAUAAUUGAUAGCUAAAUUUACUUCUUGUUCCAAAUCUUUAGGAUAUGAUUCAUGUGUGUUAUAUACAUACAUAUAUAUAUGUGUAUGUGUGUUUAUACUUACAUAUAUUUCUUUUUCUUAUUUUACUUCUGGCUAAGAUGGAGUAAUAGGGAGCAUAUUUACCCUCUAACCCUCCUGCAUGAAACAACCUCAAACCAGACAAAAUAUAUGAAACUAUGGUUUUCAGUACACUGGACAUGAGGCACGGAAUGUAAUCCCUGAAAGACAGGAAACAUAAGAUGUGUGCUGUGAGUAUCCCAGCUUACAACUUGAGAGAAUUUGAGACAGCAGUGACAAUGGAGAUAGAUAGCUUAAGGAAGCCUAGCAAGUCUCUGAAUGGAGUAGCUGUUGCUGAGAGUUCAGGUACACGAAGGUGGCUAGAGAUUGCAGGAUAGAGUACCGGCGAGGAAAGAGCUGCAUUGGAGAAAACUUUGCAAAUCUGGAGAGGGUCGCCCUUCAGUGUGUAACAAAGUGCAUGAAACUACCUGAGGCAAGGGAAAGAAACACUCAAAAGAAUUACAGCGGCAUUUAUCAACCUUUAAAAAAUUAUUAUUGACCUCAAGGAAUCUUUUUAAACAUCUUUUCUAGUCACCUCUCUAUGAAUUUUUUAAUUUUUAUUUAAUUUAAUUUAAUUUUAUUUUAUUUUUGAGACGGAGUCUUGCUCUGUCGCUCAGGCUGGAGUGCAGUGGCGCGAUCCUGGCUCACUGCAAGCUCCGCCUCCAGGGUUCAUGCCAUUCUCCUGCCUCAGCCUCCCGAGUAGCUGGGACUACAGGCACAAGCCAACAUGCCCAGCUAAUUUUUUUUUUUUUUUUUUUUUUUGUAUUUUUAGUGGAGGCAAGGUUUCACCGUGUUAGCCAGGAUGGUCUCGAUCUCUGGAUCUCAUGAUCUGCCCACCUCAGCCUCCUAAAGCGCUGGUAUCACAGGCGUAAGCCACUGCGCCCGCCCUGAAAUUUUAAUAUCGCACAUGCACUGCAUAUCUCUUUAGUACUAUACGUAUAUCUGGGCUUUACACAAAAAGAAUAUUUUUCUUCUCUUCACUUCUCCCAUCCCCCCCAAAAAAACUAAUUUCUGUCGUUUUGGGGACAAUAUUACUCUCACUGAGAGUGCAUGUUCACAUACAACCAUGAAUAGAGGUGGUUGCCAUGGGCUAUACCAGAAAUCCCCAUAAUUAAUAGGGCAUUAGGUAGAAUAUUCAUAGGGGUCUUGCCUCAGUCCUGGCAAGUCCUAGACCAUGUAUUACUAUGGCGGCCCCACUGAACAAAUCUUCAAAGAUUUGGAAAAAAAGAUCAAACCGUUUCCAAUAACUAAUUGGCAUCUCUGAGCAAAGUUCACAUGUAUUUCCAGUAACAUAAAACUAUCCAACACCAGGCCGGGCACAGUGGCUCAUGCCUGUAAUCCCAGCACUUUGGGAGGUCGAGGCAGGCAGAUCACGAGGUCGGGAGAUGGAGACCAUCCUGCUAACAAGGUGGAAACCCCGUCUCUACUAAACAUACAAAAAUUAGCCGGGCGUGGUGUUGGGCGCCUGAAGUCCCAGCUACUCGGGAGGCUGGGGCAGGAGAAUGGCAUGAACCCGGGAGGCAGAGUUUGCAGUGGGCCGAGAUUGCGCCAUUGCACUCCAGCCUGGGCAACAGAGCCAGACUCCAUCAAAAAAAAAUCCAACACCCAACGAGGUAAAAUCACAAUGUCUGGUAUACAAUAAAAAAUUACCAAGUGUGUGAAGAGGCAGAAAAAUAGGACCUAUAAUGAGGAUAAAAAUCAAUCUAAAAUGACCCAGCACAUACCCAGAUGUUAGAAUUACUAAUGAAAAAUAUUAUGACUAUAUUCCGUAUUUUCAAAGAUUAGGAUGUGACAAGAAAAGGCUUUAAUUAAACUUCGAGAGAUGACAAUGUUAAUGUAUAAGAUUAAAAAAUACAAUGGAUGUAAUUAAUGGCAGAUGAGAGUUUUCAGAAGAAAAUAUUAAUAAACUUGAAUAUAUAUAGCAGUAGAAAGCAUCCAAAAUGAAACAGAGACAGAAAAAAAACAAAGAAUAAUCAGAGUAUCGGUGAUCUGUGGGACAACUUCAGUUGCCUAAUCUGUGUGUAUUUGGAGUUCUCAAAGGAGAAAAGAGAGUGGAUGGAUAGAAAAAAAUAUUUUUAAAAAUUAAUACAUAAGCAUUUUCCACAUUUGAUGCAAACUAUAAACCCACAGACCCAGCUCAACAUCCCCAAGUAGGGGUGCUAUUAAGAAAACCACAUCACAACACAUCAUAAGCAAAUGGAUCAAAACUCAGUGUGGUAAAGAGAAAAAGACAAGUCUUACACAGAGAAGAAAAACAAGGAUGAUACCAGACUUCUUUUUGGAAGCAAUGCAAGGGGAAGGGCAGUGGAGCAACAUCUUUCAUGCUUCCAGUGAAACAUCUUCCAACCAAAAGCAGAAAACUCUCUCUCCUAGGUUUCUAUACCCAGCAAAACCGUCUUUCAAGAAAGGAUGAAACAAAGAUAUUUUUCAGACAUAGAAAAGUUAAAAGUAAUAUAUUAUCAGCAAACCUGGACUAUGAGAACAGUGUAAAAGCCUUUCAGGAAGAAGGAAAAUAAAGAAUAAUAUCUUUGUGCAGAUAGAAACAUGGAUCCACACAAAGAAAUGAAGAGCACUGGCAAUAGUAACACCAUAAGUAAAUAUACAAUACCUGCCCUUAUUACUUAAAUAUCUUUUAAAGAUAAUUGGCUGUUUAGAAAUAAUAGCAGUGUCAUGUGAGUUCUGCAGCAUGAGUAAAAGUAAAAUAUAUGACAACAAUAACCUAGAGUAAAUGGAAAUAUAGUUUAGUUUGUAAGGUUCUUAGACUGUGUGUAAAGUCGUAUAAUGCCUAUUAAAAGUUGGCUAUUACAAGUUAUCUUUAAGUUAAAACAUCUGUAUGGUGUAAUCCCUAAAGCAAAUGCUAGAGUAACAAAAACAGUGAUAAUAUUACAAUAUUACACAAUAAUAUUACAAUGCAGCGAUGAAAUAGAAUAAAUUUUUAAAUGCUUGAAAGUAGACAAAAAAGAUGAGAAAGAGGACAAAGAACAAAUGGGACAAAUAGAAAGCAAAUAGCAAGAUAUAAAAUAAAAAUCUGAUAAAUUUGACCUUAAGAUUAACAACUCUCCUUUUAAAAUACAUUGUUAAGAGAAUAAGAGUCAAGCUACAGACUGGGAGAAAAUAUUUGCAACACUUUAUUUGAAUGCUGUAAAUUUUUUUCAGAAUAUAGUUCAUAAAGAACUCUUAACAACUCAAUAAUUAGCAAAAAUAAAAUGAAAAUAAUGAAUAUAAGAAAAAAUGACGAAAAGUGCUAGGCCAGUGGACAAAAAGCACACAAAAAUGUUCAAUAUCGUUUUGUCAUUAAGGAAAUGCAAAUUAAAACCACAGUGAGUUAUUCUUCCCACUAAAAUGGUUAUGAUUAAAAAUAUUGUCAGUACCACGUGUUGUUGAGAAUAUGGAGCAAUUAUAAUUCUCAUACAUUAUUGUUGGAAUGUAAAAUGCUACAACCACUUAGGAAAAAUUGUUUAACAUUGUUUUAUAUAAUUAAGCAUACAUGAAACCUAUGACCCAACAAUUCCAAUCCUAGAUUGAAAAGAAAUGAAAACUUAUGCCCAUUAUAAGACUUACACAAGAACGUUUAUAGCAUCUUUACUUAUAAUAUCCCCAAACUGUAAACUGCCUAAAAGACCUUCAACAAGAAAAUGGACAAACAAUUUGUGUUGUAUUAAUAAUGAAAUACUCUUCAGCUAUAAAAUGGACAAAACUACUGGUAACUGCAACAAACAUGGCUGAAUCUAAAAAACCUUGUGUUGAAUGAAUAAAUCUAGACACUAUAGGGUACAUUCUGAAGUCCUAGAACAAGCGAAACUAAGAUAUAGCAGUAGAAAUUGUAUCAGUAGUUACCUGGGUUGAGGUGGGAUGGGAGUUGACUGCAGAGAAACACAAGGGAAGUUUCUGGAGUGAUGGAAAUGUUCUAUGUCUUGAUUGACUAUGGUUACAUUGGUGUGGACAUUUGUCAAAACUCUGAAUUUCAUAUUUGGAAUUUGUAUAUUUUGUAUAUAAAUUAUACUUCAAUAAAUAUGUACAUGUAUAUAUAUGUGUAUAUAUAAUACAUUUUGAUAUGUCAUGAUGUCUAUCACUUCACAGCAUAUUAUAUUUCUAUCAUACCAUAUUUACAUAAUGGAAAAAGAUGAAAAGGAUGCUGUAUUUUGGGGAAAUCACAAGAGAUUAUCACCUUUAUUUAUUUUUUAUACAAAUACAUAUAAAUCUUUCACAGUACAAUACAAAUGUCAAAAUGUGGUAUUUUCAUUGCUCUAUAAAUUCUUAUAUGUUCUAUGUAUGUAAUAAAUGUUAAAAACAGUG